AACUAAUAGUAAUAGCUCUAUGCAGGCAUGCAGCAUGCAGCGUGUUCACUGCCCUUUAAAGAAUAAAUAAGUCCUGUGAGAAAACUGUGACUGCUCUUAUCCUACAAACUUGGUUCCACAUUUUACCUCUAACCUCUGGUUUGGACAAUGAAUAGUAGAGACAUGUCCACUGCUCAGGUCCUUUUCAAUGCCCACCAUUGGCUUCAAAGUUCAAGCCUUUCAUUUUCUUGCCCCAUACAUAUUUUCAGAUUCGCUGCAUGCCACUUUCUUGCACUUGUCCUGUUAAAGAGUCCACCAUGGCUAUUUAAUAUUUAAAGGCUGAGAUCAUUUUGCGGGUUUUAGUUUAAAGGUAACCAUAGCACACACACACACAUUUAUUAUUAAUAGCAGAGACACACUGUAAGUCCUUGGGAAUCUUCUUUCCUUUUGAUGUUAGUUUCACAGGAGUGCUGCCAUCACUAGAAUUGGCUCUGAUAUUGCUAUCUGGCAAGUGGACUAGUGCAGUAACAACGGGUCCAGAAUGCUGUAAACUGUUCAUAUGGGUGGAGGUGACCAUGCUUAAAAGGGAGAUGAAGCCAGAAAGUGACAGGCCACGGAAAGUCCGGUUUCGGAUCGCGUCCUCUCACAGUGGGCGAGUUCUGAAGGAAGUGUAUGAAGAUGGGCAACCGUCAGGCUCUCUGGAUUCUGAAUGUGCCAGUAUCUGUGGGAUAGAUGGACUAGGUGAUUCCGAUGGACAGCAGAAUGGCCACAUAGAGUCAGAAGGUGAUGAGAAUGAGAAUGACCAGGAUAGCUUGCUGGUGUUAGCAAGGGCUGCCAGUGAGAAGGGUUUUGGUACAAGAAGAGUCAACAUUUUAAGCAAAAAUGGCACAGUCAGAGGCGUCAAAUACAAAGUGAGUGCUGGCCAGGCUCUAUUUAACAAUUUGACCAAAGUAUUACAGCAACCAUCAACUGAUCUAGAAUUUGACCGUGUAGUGAUUUAUACCACCUGCCUUCGUGUGGUCCGGACAACCUUUGAAAGAUGUGAACUGGUUAGAAAGAUUUUCCAAAACCAUCGCGUAAAAUUUGAAGAGAAAAACAUAGCCCUGAAUGGUGAAUAUGGAAAAGAGUUAGACGAACGAUGCCGACGAGUUUCUGAAGCUCCUUCCCUCCCUGUUGUGUUCAUUGAUGGCCAUUACCUUGGGGGUGCUGAGAAAAUUUUGUCAAUGAAUGAAUCAGGAGAACUGCAAGACAUCCUAACCAAAAUUGAGAGAGUACAGCAUCCACAUGAGUGUCCCUCUUGUGGAGGCUUUGGCUUUCUUCCAUGCUCCGUGUGCCAUGGGAGCAAGAUGUCCAUGUUUCGAAACUGCUUCACAGACUCUUUCAAAGCCCUGAAGUGUACGGCUUGCAAUGAAAAUGGUCUUCAGCGUUGUAAGAACUGUGCUGGUUAAUUGGAGCUUCUACCCAGGAAAAACCUCAUUUUAUUAAUCAAAGGCAAUACUUUGGUUUAUAUAUAUAUUUUUAAAUGGUUAUGUUUAUGGAUUAAUCAAUAAACUUUGUUUAUUAUAA